GCAUGCGCGCUCGCGCUCCCGCCCUCUAGCUGCGCUCGGCUGAGUCAGUCAGUCUGUCGGAGUCUGUCCUCGGAGCAGGCGGAGUAAAGGGACUUGAGCGAGCCAGUUGCCGGAUUAUUCUAUUUCCCCUCCCUCUCUCCCGCCCCGUAUCUCUUUUCACCCUUCUCCCACCCUCGCUCGCGUAGCCAUGGCGGAGCCGUCGGCGGCCACUCAGUCCCAUUCCAUCUCCUCGUCGUCCUUCGGAGCCGAGCCGUCCGCGCCCGGCGGCGGCGGGAGCCCAGGAGCCUGCCCCGCCCUGGGGACGAAGAGCUGCAGCUCCUCCUGUGCGGAUUCCUUUGUUUCUUCCUCUUCCUCUCAGCCUGUAUCUCUAUUUUCGACCUCACAAGAGGGAUUGAGCUCUCUUUGCUCUGAUGAGCCAUCUUCAGAAAUUAUGACUUCUUCCUUUCUUUCAUCUUCUGAAAUACAUAACACUGGCCUUACAAUACUACAUGGAGAAAAAAGCCAUGUGUUAGGGAGCCAGCCUAUUUUAGCCAAAGAAGGAAAAGACCACUUGGAUCUUCUAGAUAUGAAAAAGAUGGAAAAGCCUCAGGGGACCAGCAACAACGUAUCAGACUCUUCAGUUUCUCUUGCAGCAGGAGUUCAUUGUGACCGUCCUUCUAUUCCAGCCAGUUUCCCAGAGCAUCCUGCUUUUCUCUCAAAGAAAAUUGGUCAAGUGGAAGAGCAAAUAGAUAAAGAGACCAAGAACCCAAAUGGGGUAUCAAGUAGGGAGGCUAAAACUGCAUUGGAUGCUGAUGACAGAUUCACUUUGCUGACAGCCCAGAAACCACCUACUGAGUACUCUAAGGUAGAAGGCAUUUAUACAUAUUCUUUGUCUCCAUCCAAAGUUUCAGGAGAUGAUGUUAUUGAAAAGGAUUCCCCUGAAUCACCAUUUGAAGUAAUUAUUGACAAAGCAGCAUUUGACAAAGAAUUUAAAGACUCAUAUAAGGAGAGCACAGAUGAUUUUGGUAGCUGGUCUGUGCACACUGAUAAAGAAUCAUCCGAAGACAUUUCAGAGACUAAUGACAAGCUUUUUCCACUGAGAAAUAAAGAGGCAGGACGUUACCCAAUGUCUGCAUUGCUCAGUAGGCAGUUUUCACACACAAAUGCAGCACUGGAAGAGGUGUCCAGAUGCGUGAAUGAUAUGCAUAACUUUACUAACGAAAUACUGACUUGGGAUCUGGUUCCCCAAGUGAAACAACAGACCGAUAAAUCUUCUGACUGCAUCACAAAAACUACAGGACUUGACAUGAGUGAAUAUAAUUCAGAAAUUCCAGUUGUAAAUCUUAAAACUAGCACUCAUCAGAAAACUCCUGUAUGUUCUAUUGAUGGGAGCACUCCCAUCACUAAAUCAACAGGUGAUUGGGCAGAAGCAUCUCUCCAGCAAGAAAAUGCUAUUACUGGAAAACCUGUACCUGACUCUUUGAAUUCCACAAAAGAAUUCAGUAUCAAAGGUGUGCAAGGCAAUAUGCAGAAACAGGAUGACACACUUGCAGAAUUACCUGGAUCUCCACCUGAGAAAUGUGACUCUUUGGGUUCUGGAGUGGCCACAGUGAAAGUGGUUUUACCUGAUGACCACCUGAAAGAUGAAAUGGACUGGCAGAGCUCUGCAUUGGGAGAAAUCACAGAAGCUGAUAGUUCUGGUGAGUCUGAUGACACAGUAAUAGAGGACAUCACAGCAGAUACAUCAUUUGAAAAUAACAAAAUUCAGGCUGAAAAACCUGUUUCCAUUCCAAGUGCUGUUGUAAAAACAGGUGAAAGAGAAAUCAAAGAGAUUCCCAGUUGUGAGAGAGAAGAAAAAACAUCUAAAAACUUUGAAGAAUUGGUCAGUGACUCUGAGCUGCAUCAAGAUCAGCCUGAUAUUCUUGGAAGGAGUCCAGCUAGUGAGGCAGCAUGUUCAAAAGUACCCGAUACGAAUGUCUCCUUAGAAGAUGUGAGUGAAGUUGCUCCUGAAAAGCCUAUUACUACUGAGAACCCCAAACUUCCUUCAACAGUGUCUCCAAAUGUUUUUAAUGAGACAGAAUUCUCAUUAAAUGUGACAACAUCUGCCUAUUUGGAGUCAUUACAUGGGAAAAAUGUUAAACAUAUAGAUGAUUCCUCCCCAGAGGACCUGAUAGCAGCCUUUACAGAAACCAGAGAUAAAGGAAUAGUAGAUAGUGAAAGAAAUGCUUUUAAAGCAAUAUCAGAGAAGAUGACAGACUUUAAAACAACUCCUCCUGUAGAAGUCUUACAUGAAAAUGAGUCCGGUGGUUCUGAAAUUAAAGACAUUGGAAGCAAAUACAGUGAACAAAGCAAAGAAACAAAUGGAAGUGAGCCUCUAGGUGUUUUCCCUACCCAAGGUACUCCAGUAGCAUCUCUUGACUUAGAACAAGAACAGCUCACAAUUAAGGCUCUUAAAGAAUUAGGUGAAAGACAGGUUGAGAAGUCAACUUCUGCACAGCGUGACGCAGAAUUGCCUUCUGAAGAAGUACUGAAGCAAACUUUCACAUUUGCUCCAGAAUCUUGGCCACAGAGAUCAUAUGACAUCCUAGAACGUAAUGUCAAGAAUGGAUCUGAUCUUGGGAUUUCCCAGAAGCCCAUCACUAUCAGAGAAACUACUAGGGUAGAUGCUGUUUCCAGCCUUAGCAAGACUGAAUUGGUAAAAAAGCAUGUCCUAGCAAGACUUCUGACAGACUUCUCAGGCUUUUACUGGACCUGACCUUCCUGCAUAUAACUGGACAAAAUUUUUAAAAAACAAAGACCCGAAGGCACUGGAGGAUGAACGGGAGCAGUCAGAUUCUGAAAGAGAGUUGACACAUGUAAGAAGAGACAGCAUGAAAUUAGUUUUUUAUUUUUACUGCUUUUAGCUAGAGGACAGGCUGAAGUGGGCACCUGACAGGCUGGCUUAAACCUUCAUAGAAAACCUAAGCAGUGGACAGCAUUUGGGUCAGCCACAACCACUGAGUCAGUGGAAUGUAAGGGGAGGAGGAAUCUUGGAAGGGAGAGAUCCAGAGAGUGACAGCCUAAAAUUCUGUAGAUAAAAUAAACUGUGUUUAAGCCUCUGUUUAAUUGUAAACCACACUUAACACAAAAGAUUAUAAGCAGCACAACUAGAGAUGAAAGAAGUGAACUGGGCCGGGUGCAAUGGCCCACGCCUGUAAUCCCAGCACUUUGGGAGGCCAAGGCGGGUGGAUCACGAGAUCAGGAGUUCAAGACCAGCCUGGUCAAGCUGGUGAAACCCCAUCUCUACUAAAAAUACAAAAAUUAGCCGGGCACAUUGGCAGGCGCCUGUAAUCCCACCUACUCAGGUGGCUGAGGCAGGAGAAUCGCUUGAACCCCUGGGGGUGGAGGUUGCAGUGAGCCAAGAUCAUGCCAUUGCACUACAGCCUGGGUGACAGAGUAAGACUCCGUCUGAAAAAAAAAAAAAAAAAGAAGAAGUGAGCCGAGUUUGUAGUUUGAAGGCCAGGCACAGUGGCUCAUGCCUGUAAUCCCAGUACUUCAGGAGGCUGAAGCAGGUGGAUCACUUGAGCCCAAGAGUUCAAGGCCAGCCUGGGCAGCAUGGUGAAACCCCAUCUCCACUAAAAAAUACAAAAUUAAGCCAGGCAUGGUGGCCUGUGCCUGUAGUCCCUGAGCCCAGGGAGGUCAGGGGUGCAGAUCGCACCACUGCACUCCAGCCUGGGUGACAGAGUAAGACUCUAUCUUGAAAAAAAAAGUUUGCAGUUUGAAUCUAACCAAAUUUAUUACAUGUUAAAACAAAAGUAAUGAUACUCUCCAGAGGAAUAGAACACAGUCUGGAAUUUGUACAGCAUAAUAUUCACAAUGUCCAGGAUAUAAUCCAAAACUACAUGUUUUAAGAACCAAGAAAUUAUAACUCAGUCUGAAGAAAAAGAGACAAUCGAUAGAAACUAACUGCAUGUGUUGGAAUUAGGAGUCAGGAUUUUAAGGGUUUUCAUUUUAAUCACUCAAAGAAGUAAAGGGAAAUAUUCUUGUAUUGAAUAAAAAAGAAAAUCUCAACCUAGAAAUCGAAACAAAAAAGAGUCAGGUGGGGAUUCUAGAACUGUAAAAUAUAACCACUGAAAUUAAAAUUCAGCAGGUGACCUUAACAGCAAAAUGGAGAUGACAGGGGAAGAAGCUGGUGAACUUGAUAGCAUACUAAAGAACAGAAAGAACACAUAUUUUUUAAAAGUGUCACCAGAGCUUCAGAACCCUGUGGGACAAUAUCAAAAGACCUAACUUUGGCCAGGCACAGUGGCUCACGUCUGUAAUCCCACCACUUCAGCACUUAGGGAGGCCGAGGCAGGAGGAUCACUUGAGCCCAGGAGUGCGAGACCUGCAAAACCUAUUUUUUAUAAUUGGAGUCCUAGCAGGAGAGGAAAGUGAGAGAGAGACUGGAGAAGGACAUAUUUAAAGAUAAAAUGGCUGAAAUUUUCUUAAAUUUUAUGAAAGGCACAUUUACUGAUGAAAGACGCUCAUCAAACACCACCUACUAGGAUAAUUACAAAGAAAACCAUACCUUGGUGUAUGUGUCGGGGUCCCCAAGAUAACCAUCAGGGCCAGUGAUUUGCUAGAAGGACCCAUAGGACUCAUAAACUGUAAACUAGCAGUUAAUGGUUUAUUACAGCAAAAGGACAUAGGUUAGAAUUGGCCAGAGGAAAAGACACACGGGAUAAAAUCUAGGAGAGAUCAGAUGCAAGCUUCCAGGUAUUGAAUGGAGUCAUACAGGGAUGUACUUAAUUCUUUUACAGUGAUGCGUGAUAACAUGUGCAAAGGAUUCCCAACCAAGGAAGCUCUUUCAAUCUUUGGUGUCUAGCACGGCAUGCAGUGCCCAUAUGACUGAACUCAGCUACUCAGACCCCAGACCCCCAGAGCAAAAACAUGUACUGGCAAUAAAUCAUAUUGUUAGGAUAAAUUUAUCUGAUACAGCAUGGCCUAAGACCUCAGGCAUGCAAAAAUACUUAUGAAGCAGAAUAUUCAAAGGGCUCAGAGGCCAUCUCCAAGGAGCCAGCAAAGGGCUAGUCCUGAAGACAGACCUUUCUUUGGCAUGUGCAGGGCUUGGCAUUCUAGGCCUGCUGAGUUUUCACCCUUUCCUAUACAGUGUAUCGUAGUCAAGUUGCUGAAAACCAAAAAUAAGGAGAAAAUCUUGAAAGUAGCUAGAGAAGAGGCUGGGCGCGGUGGCUCACGCCUGUAAUCCCCACACGUUGGAAGGCCGAGACAGGUGGGUCACAAGGUCAGGAGUUCGAGACCAGCCUGACCAACAUGGUAAAACCCCAUCUCUACUAAAAAUACAAAAAUUAGCCGGGGUGGCAGUGCACACCUGUAAUCCCAGCUACCCAGGAGGCUGAGGCAAGAGAAUCACUUGAACCCAGGAGGCGGAGGUUGCAGUGAGCCGGGAUUGCGCCACUGCACUCCAGCCUGGGCGACAGAGCGAGACUCCGUCUCAAAAAAAAAAAAAAAAGAAAAAAGAAAAGAAAGUAGCUAGAGAAGAAUGACACAGGGAAAUGACAAUUAUAAUUAGAGCUUACUUCUUACUAGAAACCACAGAUGUUUAAAAGGCAGUAGAGUAACAUCUUAUAAAGUGCCCAACAGGGAAAAAAAACCUGUCAACCCAGGUUUCUGUAUUCAGGAAAAAAACAACAAAAAAAACAAAAAAACUGCAAGAUUAAAAGACAUUUUUAGAUAAAAGAAAACUAAAAGAAUUCUACCAGAAGACCUGCACUACAAGAAAUGCUAAAGGAAGUUUUUCAGAUUAAAGGAAAGUGAUACCAAAUAAAAACUCAGACCUUUAGGAAGGAAUGAAGAGAAUUGGAAGUGGUAAACACCUGGGUGAAUAUGAAAGGCUUAUUUUUUUCCUCUUAAUUUCUUAAAAUAUAUAGGAUUGCUUAAAGCAAAAAUUGUAAUAACGUGUAUAGAGGUUAUGAUGUUUAUUUCUUAGGACAAUUAUAACAGAAAAAAACGAGUAUAUGGACUGUACUAUAGCAAAGGUUUCUGCUUUUUUUUUUUUUUUUUUUUUUUGUUUGUUUGAGACAGGAUCUGGCUCUGUGGCUCUGUAUCCCAGUCUGGAGUGCAGUGGUGCAAUCAUGACUCACUGCAACCUAGACCUCCUGGGCUCAAGCAAUCCUCGUGCCUCAGCCUCCCAUGUACCUGGGACCACAGGUGCAUGCCACCACACCUAGCUAAUUUUUUUAUUUUUUUAGUAGAGACAGAGUCUCAUUAUGUUGCCAACACUGGCAUUGAUCUCCUGGGCUCAAGUAAUCCUCCCACCUUGGUCUCCCAAAGUGCUGGGAUUAUAGGCAUGAGCCACUAUGCCCAGCCUGUUUCUACAUUUUUAAUGUAAUGGUACUAUAAAUAUAUAUAUAUUUGGAGACAGGGUCUCGCUCUGUCACCCAGGCUGUAGUGCAGUGAGUGGCAUGAACACAGCUCACUGUACCUCAACCUCCCAGGCUCAAGCAAUCCUCCCACUUCACCUUUUUGGGACUAUAGGUAUAUGCCACGAUGCCCAACUAGUUUUUAAAUUAAUUUUAUUUUUAUUUAUUUUUUGAGACAGAGUCUCACUCUGUCACCCAGGCUGGAGUGCAGUGGCGUGAUCUCAGCUCACUGCAACCUCUGCCUUCCGGGUUCAAGGGAUUCUCCUCCCUCAGCCUCCCAAGUAGCUGGGAUUACAGGCACUCACCACCACGCCUGGCUUAUUUUUGUAUUUUUAGUAGAGAUGAGGUUUCACCAUGUUUGUCAGGCUGAUCUCAAACUCCUGACCUCUAGUGAUCCACCCUCCUCGGCCUCCCAAAGUGCUGGGAUCAUAGGCGUGAGCCACCGUGCUCGGCCAAAAGAUGUUAUUUAAAUAUAAAGACACAGGUUGAAAGUAAAUGGAUGGAAAAGAUAUCCCAAAAAAUUUAUAAAUGUAUGCCAUGCAAACAGUAAGCAUAAGAAGAUGAAAGCUUUUAUCAGAAAUAAAUAAGGGACAUCUUAUCAUGAUAAAAGAUACCAGGAAGUCUUGACAGUUAUAAGUGUGUAUGUGCCUAAUAAUGGCUUCAAAAUACACAAAGCAAAAAUUGACAGAAUUGGCUGGGCAAUGGCCCAUGCCUGUAACCCCAACAUUUUGGGAGGCCAAGGUGAGAAGAUCACUUGAGACUAGUUUGAGACCAGCCUGGGCAACAUAACCCUUAACCCAACAUAACCCUACCCUGGAGUUUUUUUGUAGAGACCCCCAUCUCUACAAAAAUUCAAAAAUUAACUGGUUUGGUGGCAUGCA